CCUUCCCCAUAUCCUUUUCUUUUUAUUUGCCAGAAAAGUGCAGUUCUCCAGAAGCCAGCAGGCCAACCAUGGGCGUCUCCCUCCCUCCCUCCCUAAGCACACUCAGCACCCAGGAGGGACAUGAGCACCCACAGCCUGGGAAGGUCCCUCAGCGGCCGGGAGGGACAUAAGCACACACAGCCCGGGAAGGUCCCAGAGCAGGCUGGGUGCUCCUUGCUUACGGAGGCCCCACCAGGGCCUGGCAGGGCACCCAGAAGAUGAGGGCUUUAAAGAGCUCUCUUUGUCCCCAUGUGGCUCCUUCUACCAUGCUCCCGGCAAGCUAAUGUUCUCAGUGGCUCUUUUUUUUUUUUAACAACUCUUAUUUUCAAAUAAGAAUAAAUAUGUGUGUCUGUUCUCUGGGGGUUUAGGCAGCCCCGAGCUGACCCUGUGACUGGGGAGGGAUUGAUGGCCCCGUCUCACCGGGAAGCCAGGUGCAUCUUUUACUAAAGGUGGUUUCUGAAUGAUGAAUGGCUUUCUCACGAACAUAACACUGUUGAUUGUAUUUACAAACAAUUCAUUUUCACGUUCUGUUGAUUCUGCCCCAGCCGUCCCUCCUGUUGCCUCCACAGAUGAUGCAUUGGUGGCUAUUACCACCAUUGAUGAAGGCGUCCUGCUCGCCCUGUGGUACCUGUUACUCCAUUCAUCACAGUUGAGCAGCCUGCGUGCAGCGGGAGAGCGUGUUCUCUUCGGGCCUUGCAGUUAUUUAUCCUUGAAUUUGUGUGGGUUUGUGCACCUCUAAAUACAGGUGCAAACCCACACUCCAAGAUCUUAACAGGCGCAACAGUGGCCAAAAUACACGGCCAGUUAAAUUCUUGGGGUUUAGCCAGUCCCCCAAAGCCCACCUCUUCCACUCCACAUUCUAAAAAAAUACCGAUGCGCAUAAACAGUGUCAGCAACCUCCACUAAUUAAGGCUUCCAACCAGAAGGAAAGCUGAAGUAAGUACCAGCGAUCAGCAUCAAAUCAUCAACUUUUAGGGCUGACCUAAAAGACCCCAAGCCUGAAUGCCCCAGCACCCACUGGGCAAGGGGCAGCCAGUCCCCAGCAUGGCCUAAUCCAGGCCAAGCAGGAAAUUUCUGGAAUCAGCUGCUUUUUCCACAUUUCUCUAUCUAGACCCCCUCCUCCUGGCUGCCUCUCUGGUUCAGUGGUGGCGUUCCCCUGAGCUUGACCGGGCUCUGCAGAUGGGCUGGCAUGCAUGGAAGAAGCUGGCGCUGUGAGGAGUCCUGGCUUCCCGCUCACAGCCAUUGGGCCUUGGGUGAGUCAGUCAGUCUCUCCAGACCUUGAGGUCUUCACCCAGGACAUGUGGAGGCUCAGAAAGGAGCCCAGGUUCCUGCCCAUCUGGAAAAUCUGCAUGUUCCUGGUUGCAGCAAGAGUCUGCCAGGCUCACACUUGCAAAGUACUGGUCCAUAUAAAAGCAUAAAGCAGGCCAGGCACAGCGGCUCACACCUGUAAUCCCAGCACUUUGGGAGGCCAAGGUGGGCCAAUUGCUUGAGCCCAGAGUUUGAGACAAGCCUGGGCAACAUAGCGAGACCCCAUCUCUACAAAAAAUACAAAAGUUAUCUGGAUGUGGUGGCGCAUGCAAGCGGUCCCUGCUACUUGGGAGACCGAGGUGGGAGGAUUGCCUGAGCCUAGGAGGUUGAGGCUGCAGUGAAGUGAGCUGUGAUCACACCACUGCACUCCAGCCUGGGCGACAGAGAGCCACCCUGUCUCAAAAAAAAAAAAAAAGGCCAGUCACAGUGGCUCACACCUAUAAUCCCAACACUUUGGGAGGCCAAGGCAGGCAGAUCACUGGAGCUCAGAAGUUCAAGACCAGCCUGGGCAACAGGGCGAAACCCUGUCUCAAUUUUUUUUUCUUUAUAAAUUACAAAAGAGAAAACGAGCAUAAAGCAGCCCCAUCAGCAAUUAUCACCUCAUCUGCAAAAGGUCCCGGCGCUCACUGCCGUGCCCCUCCCGCCGCUGUCCAGUUCCCUGCCUGUCACACCAAAAUUCUCCUCUACUUUCUCACCUCCCAUCCUUUCAUUUUUCCCCCUAAAUUUUUAAACUUCAGAAGUGCACAAUACACAUGUAACAAACCCACACAUGUACCUCCAAAUCUAAAAUAAUUUAAAAAAACAAAAAGGAAACUCUAAAUUUUUUGAGUGCAGUGAUACAUUCUUGCUGUGCCAAAUCCAGUAACACAGAAGCAUGCAAAGAAAAAGGCAGCACCACCCCCCUCCAACACACACACACACACACACACACGCACACACGCACAUAUGCACGCACACACACGCACACGCACACACGCACACGCACACACUCCAGCCUGGGCGACAAGAGCAAGACUCCAUCUCAAUAAAUAAAUAAAGAAAAUAGUAAUUGAAUAUUUUCCUUCAGGAAACAGCACCCUGCAGGGAGGGGAAGUCUUAUGACCCUCAAAGUUUGAGAGCCUCUCUUAACUUCCCAAUGGCCUCUGUCUGCUGAACCAAGAAGCCUGCAAAACAAAUACGUAAGAACUGGAUACCAUUUCAGUCACACAUGCUUGCUGACAGUCACUGAUAUGGUAAUGCCUCCUGUACACAUAGCUGACUCUGAAGACUGCUAAGAGGGUUUGGGUCUCUGCUGUACAGGACCUUGGCAGCCUGCAAGGAGAUGACUCACAUGGAAGUCCCCACACAAGUGCACCCAGUGUGAACUUUGGAAGCAUCGGCCCAUGCUCAGGCCCACAGGUAAGAUGGCCAGGAGCCCCUAACCUUGAGGAAACUUGAACCACAGAGCUGCUGGCGAAGGGGGUGGGUGAAGGUCUCAUGUAGCCUGUGUGAUUCAGGCAGAAGUGAGAAGGACGGGUGGGAACCCACCAAGUGGACGACAAGCUGAAGGGCUCCCAGGGAGCAGACACUUCAAGGGCCCCAAAAGGCCAGGAGAAAGAAAAAAAAAAGCCGGGUAUGGUGGCUCAUCCCUGUAAUCCAGCACUUUUGGGAGGUUGAGGCAGAUGAAUUGCUUGAGCCCAGAAGUUUGAGACCAGCCUGGGCCUGGGCAAUGUGGCGAAACCCUGUCUCUACAAAAUAUACAAAAAUUAGCCGGGUGUGGUGGUGCAAGCCUGUAGUCCCAGCUAUUCAGGAGGCUGAGGUGGGAGGAUCACAUGAGCCCAGGAGGUGGAGGCUGCAGUGAGCUGUGAUCGUACCACUGCACUCCGGCCUGGGGAACAGAGUGAGGCCCUGUCUCAAAAGGCCAGGAGUGGAAGACAGGCCCUAGCCAGGAGGUUUCGCGUGGCUGGCAGGGGCCUUAUGAGAAGGCUGUUGCUGGGAGGGGCCUGCUGCAGAUGGCUGCGGCAGACCACGGAGCUUAGCCUUCAGGAUUUAGAUCUGGGGAUGACAGGCUCCUGUGUGCUUGUUGCGGAGCCGGGAGCACAGGCACCAGAAUGAUCCCAGGGCUCAGCUCCAAGGCUCCGCUGGGCCUGUGGUGGGGCAGUGAACGUGGACAAGACCUGGGCUUCAGAGGAACUUGAUGACCAGGAGCCGUGGUUACCGCCUGUGCCCUGGCCUUCCUGCUCUUCAAAGGGUGUGUUCUGAGCUGAGGCGAGACCCACACGAAAUCCGAGCGGGCUCCGGAGUCACCAGACACCUAGGGAAGUAUGGAAGGCCCGGAAGGACACACACAGCCGGGGCUGUGACUCCCUGACGCAGAUCCAGUGCGGCCAGCUGCAGAGCCGCAGGGCCCAGAUUCACCAGCAGAUUGACAAGGAGCUGCAGAUGCGGACGGGCGCUGAGAACCUCUACAGAGCCACCAGCAACAACCGGGUGAGAGAGACGGUCGCCCUGGAGCUGAGCUACGUCAACUCCAACCUGCAGCUGCUGAAGGAGGAGCUGGAGGAGCUCAGCGGUGGCGUGGACCCUGGCCGGCAUGGGAGCGAAGCUGUCACUGUCCCCAUGAUCCCCCUGGGCCUGAAGGAGACCAAGGAGCUGGACUGGUCUACACCGCUGAAGGAGCUGAUCUCAGUGCACUUUGGAGAGGACGGCGCCUCCUACGAGGCAGAAAUCAGGGAGCUGGAGGCCCUGCGGCAGGCCAUGCGGACCCCCAGCCGGAAUGAGUCGGGCCUGGAGCUGCUCACAGCCUAUUACAACCAGCUGUGCUUCCUGGAUGCGCGCUUCCUCACCCCUGCCAGGAGCCUCGGGCUCUUCUUCCACUGGUACGACUCGCUUACUGGGGUCCCGGCCCAGCAGCGUGCCCUGGCCUUCGAGAAGGGCAGCGUUCUCUUCAACAUCGGUGCCCUCCACACGCAGAUUGGGGCGCGCCAGGACCGCUCCUGCACCGAGGGUGCCCGCCGCGCUAUGGAGGCCUUCCAGAGGGCCGCUGGGGCCUUCAGCCUCCUGAGGGAGAACUUCUCCCAUGCGCCGAGCCCAGACAUGAGCGCUGCGUCCCUCUGCGCACUGGAGCAGCUCAUGAUGGCCCAGGCCCAGGAAUGUGUGUUUGAGGGCCUCUCACCACCUGCCUCCAUGGCCCCCCAAGACUGCCUGGCCCAGCUGCGCCUGGCGCAGGAGGCCGCCCAGGUGGCAGCCGAGUACAGGCUAGUGCACCGGACCAUGGCCCAGCCACCCGUCCACGACUACGUGCCUGUCUCCUGGACUGCCCUGGUGCAUGUCAAGGCCGAGUACUUCCGCUCCCUGGCCCACUACCACGUAGCCAUGGCCCUCUGCGACGGCUCCCCAGCGACCGAGGGAGAGCUCCCCACGCACGAGCAGGUCUUCCUGCAGCCCCCCACCUCCUCUAAGCCCCGAGGCCCUGUGCUGCCGCAGGAGCUGGAGGAGCGCAGGCAGCUUGGCAAGGCACACCUGAAGCGUGCCAUCCUGGGGCAGGAGGAGGCGCUGCGGCUGCACGCCCUGUGCCGCGUCCUGCGCGAGGUGGACCUGCUUCGGGCUGUGAUCUCCCAGACGCUGCAGCGCUCACUGGCCAAGUAUGCGGAGCUCGACCGUGAGGAUGACUUCUGUGAGGCUGCCGAGGCCCCGGACAUCCAGCCUAAGACCCACCAGAAGCCAGAGGCCAGGAUGCCACGCCUGUCCCAGGGGAAGGGGCCUGACAUCUUCCAUCGGCUGGGGCCCCUGUCUGUGUUCUCAGCCAAGAACCGGUGGCGGCUGGUGGGGCCCGUCCACCUGACCCGAGGAGAGGGCGGCUUUGGCCUCACGCUUCGGGGAGACUCGCCUGUCCUCAUCGCUGCCGUCAUUCCAGGGAGCCAGGCCGCGGCGGCUGGCCUGAAGGAGGGCGACUACAUUGUGUCAGUGAAUGGGCAGCCAUGCAGGUGGUGGAGACACGCGGAGGUGGUGACGGAGCUGAAGGCUGCGGGAGAGGCGGGCGCCAGCCUGCAGGUGGUGUCGCUGCUGCCCAGCUCUAGACUGCCCAGCUUGGGGGACCGCCGGCCCGUCCUGCUGGGCCCCAGGGGGCUUCUAAGGAGCCAGAGGGAGCAUGGUUGCAAGACCCCGGCAUCCACGUGGGCCAGUCCCCGGCCCCUCCUCAACUGGAGCCGAAAGGCCCAGCAGGGCAAGACUGGAGGCUGCCCCCAGCCCUGUGCCCCAGUGAAGCCAGCUCCGCCCUCAUCCUUGAAGCACCCAGGGUGGCCGUGAGGGCCAGGAUCCCUGCACGCCUCAGCCCUGGCUCCAGCUGGCAGCAAGCACCGAGCAUGCCCUCCCCACCCAGAGGACCUCCGGGCAAUGCCUGUCCCGCCUCAUGCUGGAGGCUGCCUCGGGCACCUGCCUGCCCAUUAAAGACUGGUCAGACCUGUCUGAGCCCAGUGAUGGGAGCUGUGGCCUCUUCACCCACACACAGAAGGAUGCCAGUCCCUCUGUCGGUCUGAGGUCAGCUUCCUGGGGCUGCCCCACCCUGAGGGCUCCUUACAGGGUGCUCCUCACAGCCAUCCCAUCUGUACCCCCGGGCUCUGUCCACCCUGCUGCUGCCCUGGGCACAGACCCUGAGGUCUCAGUCCUGCCUCCAGCCAAGUUUCUGCCUGGUGCCCAGUGAUUCCUGCUGGGCACCCCUUCGCUCACUGCCCCUCCACCAUGCAGCAGCCAGACACACCCACAGCACCCGCAGACCUCUAGGCCGGGUCCCAGACAUGGCCUUCCCCCAAAAUACUUCCUGCUGUCCUGUCUGUGCACAGAGCAAGGGACUCCCCACCUCUGCGCCCUGUGCUGGUCAUCAUGGGCUCUGUGCUGGUCAACCCAGCAAGUGUCCCGUUUGCCCAGGAGUCCCUGGUGUCGUGGCCCAGGUCUCAUGGUGGCCCUAAGCCUGCCAGCCCUGCUGCCCGCCUUGCUGUCCUGCUCUGAGCAUGGGUGCCACCCUCCAGCUCCUGGGCGUGUCACUUCUCUCUGAGCCUGGGGCCUGCAUGGGCCCCCAGCCCUCCCCAGCCUGCUUGGGCCGCUCCUGCUGGCCUCCACAGGCCGUGAGCUGUCAGUGUCUCAAGCAGGGGAAGUGAGGGCUGCCUCCAGGCCUCCGUGUACUGGGUGGACAAUGGCCCCCAAAGGCCGUCGGCAAGAACACCACCUCCAGGACCCCUACAGCAGUGGGCUCAGGACUUGGGCACCAAGAGGAGAGGGUGGGAAGGGCUGCAGAGUCAGGGCUGCACCCAAGAGGAGCCACGGAGCCGGAGCCGGAGCGGAGGCCCCCACCGAGGGCCCCAGGGCCUGGCAGGUUCCGGAAGAGACAGGGCCAGCGGGAGUCAUUCCCUGCAGCCACUAGGGGGCAGCCGCCACCCGCUCAGCAGCCCUGGGAGGCGGCACGGGCAGGUGCGCCUUGGGAGGGCUGAGGCAAAGACCCCGGGUAGAAAGGCGGCCCCCAGCUCUGCGAGACCCCUGCCCUCUUGUCCAGUCCCUUCCGAGGGUCCGCAGGUGAGAGCAGCCUGCCCUGCAUCCCAGGCUCUGGUUCCAGGGUCCAGGGCCCUGCGCUGCCACCUCCCUCGUGCUUCAGCCAAGAAAAUGGGGGUGCAAGUAGGGUGUUUGGGGUCCCAGAGACGCAGGCGCCGCGGCGCGAUCUUCCUGGGCAGGAGGGCAGGGCUCCCCAACCUGCCUGAGCCGGGGUGGGGGUCCAGGUCCCCCACUUGCCCUUGUGGGAAAAUCCCUGUCUCAGCAGAAUGGGCCAAGGUCACGCAGGUCUCCCCAGCACGUGUUAAUUUGGUUAAUAAAACUGUGGAUCAAGGAG